AUCAGUUUGCGGAACCGCCUUGGUAGAAGGAGAGAAGGGGAGUGGAGGAAGCACGGGACUGGAGGGACCAAAGUUCCCCGAUGGCGGCCCAGGGGUGCGCGGCAUCGCGGCUGCUCCAGCUGCUGCUGCAGCUUCUGCUUCUACUGUUGCUGCUGGCGGCGGGCGGGGCGCGCGCGCGGUGGCGCGGGGAGGGCACCAGCGCACACUUGCGGGACAUCUUCCUGGGCCGCUGCGCCGAGUACCGCGCACUGCUGAGUCCCGAGCAGCGGAACAAGAACUGCACAGCCAUCUGGGAAGCCUUUAAAGUGGCGCUGGACAAGGAUCCCUGCUCCGUGCUGCCCUCAGACUAUGACCUUUUUAUUAACUUGUCCAGGCACUCUAUUCCCAGAGAUAAGUCCCUGUUCUGGGAAAAUAGCCACCUCCUUGUUAACAGCUUUGCAGACAACACCCGUCGUUUUAUGCCCCUGAGCGAUGUUCUGUAUGGCAGGGUUGCAGAUUUCUUGAGCUGGUGUCGACAGAAAAAUGACUCUGGACUCGAUUACCAAUCCUGCCCUACAUCAGAAGACUGUGAAAAUAAUCCUGUGGAUUCCUUUUGGAAAAGGGCAUCCAUCCAGUAUUCCAAGGAUAGUUCUGGGGUGAUCCACGUCAUGCUGAAUGGUUCAGAGCCAACAGGAGCCUAUCCCAUCAAAGGUUUUUUUGCAGAUUAUGAAAUUCCAAACCUCCAGAAGGAAAAAAUUACACGAAUCGAGAUCUGGGUUAUGCAUGAAAUUGGGGGACCCAAUGUGGAAUCCUGCGGGGAAGGCAGCAUGAAAGUCCUGGAAAAGAGGCUGAAGGACAUGGGGUUCCAGUACAGCUGUAUUAAUGAUUACCGACCAGUGAAGCUCUUACAGUGCGUGGACCACAGCACCCAUCCUGACUGUGCCUUAAAGUCACCCAAGAGGCUAUGUGGGACAUUAGGAGUGCGACCCAGAGCAGAACCAUACAACCGCCGGUUCUAGCCUUUGUACAAGGAAACUGUGGGAACCAUGAUGGGGAAGAUACUGACUGUCAGAGAGUCCAAAGAUGUAAAUGCCUUCCACUCCCACAGCAAGGAAGCCGAAAUCUCCAGAGGCUCUGGCAAGAGUUGAGUCAAUUGCAUGCCUGCCUAGUCCAGCUCCGUCCACAUGAAUGCUCUCCACAAGCUUCAGAGGAAACAGGAUAAAAUGGACUCCCAAAUAUUUAGGGUGGUGAAAAUACUCUGCAUGAUACUAGAAUUGUGGAUACAGGUGAUUAUAUAUGUGUCCAAACCUACAGAAGGUACAACACCAAGGGUGAACCCUCAGGUAAACUACAGAGGCUGGGUGACCAUGAUGUUUCAAUGUCGGUUCAUUAGUUGUGACAAAUGCACCACUCCACCACUCUGGUGGGGAUGCUGCCAGUGGGGGAGGCUAUGUAUGUGUGGGGACAGAGCGUAUGUGGGAAGCUCUGUACUUUCUGCUCAAAUUUGCUGUGAACCUAAAACUGCUCUAAACAUUAAAGCCUAUUCAAAAAAAUGAAAGCCUAAUUUGAAAAGGAAUUUCAGACACUUGGGAAAAAGAAUAAUGACGUCUAUAAGUCAUUCUUUGAUAAGAGAGUCGGUCAGUCUGGUGUGUCUAGUAAGGUAGCAGAGGGACAUUCACAAAGACCGGAGAAUACAAAGAUGUUAAACAGGGUGAGGAGUCUAUGAUGUUGGUCAGUAUAAAAGGAGAAAAAGAUCCUAAAAACAUUCCUAAAUAUUGUUUGAUUUAAAAAUAUAUGUUGGAAGGCAAGAGAGUUUGAUAAAAAAAUAAAAAUAAAAAUAAAAAACCUUGAUGGGAAGUGGGAAUGACCACACGUUAGCCAGCUGAUAGCUUACCUGUUUGAAGUUCAGCUUCCACACGAUUGUUACAGACGGAACUGUGUUCCCUCAAAUUCAUAGUUCGUUAUGGCCACCCUGGUAAGCUAACACAACAAUGAAAAUUUCCAAAGUAAAGACUAGAAGCAGGCAUGUGCCAAGUGAACACUAGCUUUUUUUAUUUCUCCUGCUGUGAAAAUUGAGGUUUGCCAAAGGUGCCAAAUGAACAUGGCUGAUUGAGAAGUAAUCCCAGUUCCACUAACCUGAGAGACAGCCCAGGCAAGCGGACCUAGCUCCUAAUGCUCAUUUCCAUUUCAGUCUUUCUGAAGUUUCCCAGGGUGAGAAAGUGGAACUCAGGACAAUGAAUCAUCAUUGGAGACUCUGCAGUUGCUAGAACUUAAUUCACAGGCAUUUGAAACCCAGAACUCAGCCUUACUCUUCUCAGGAGACUUUUGGCACCAAAGAGAAGGGCAAAUUGAAAGCCCAUGCUGGAGAACAGGGCACAGCUAUUGCUGAGACUGGGAGCUUGUUUUUAAAGACCUGGCAAGGGUUUCAAACACCCACAUGCAUAACCAAUGAAGCAGGUUGGAAAAUCUGAACUAUGCUAAUUUCACCAUAAUUACUCAUUACUUGAAGUCUUAUGUAUUUGUGUUUUCUUGGUAGUCUCUUUAAAACAUGUUUCAAUAUGAAACGUAUAUGUAUUAAAUCACUCCGCUUAGAAUUUUAGGAAUAUAGUUUUGUUUUUCCCCCUAAAAGAUGUAGAAUGCAGCAGGUUCUCUAAAGCACAUGUAUUCUUUGUUACGUGAUUUGGUUCUUUGGAACUUCUUUUAUCAUGUAGCUAUUAAAGGGUAGCUGUCAGAAUUACCCAAA